ACUUCUCCAGCCAGCGCCCCAGCCCUCCCGCCGCCCGCUCGCAGGUCCCGAGGAGCGCAGGUGAGGCGGCACCCCACUCCCGGCGGCCCCCGGGCCUCCUUCCGCACGCACCCCGAGCUGCCUCCGCACAGUUGGAGGAGCGUAGGAGGGACCCCCACCCAGGGAUGACACUCCAGGAAGGGGACUGCAGAGGAAGCCAGACUGUGUCCCUGACAAUGGGAACAGCCGACAGUGAUGAGAUGGCCCCGGAGGCCCCACAGCACACCCACAUCGAUGUGCACAUCCACCAGGAGUCUGCCCUGGCCAAGCUCCUGCUCACCUGCUGCUCUGCGCUGCGGCCCCGGGCCACCCAGGCCAGGGGCAGCAGCCGGCUGCUGGUGGCCUCGUGGGUGAUGCAGAUCGUGCUGGGGAUCUUGAGUGCAGUCCUAGGAGGAUUUUUCUACAUCCGCGACUACACCCUCCUCGUCACCUCGGGAGCUGCCAUCUGGACAGGGGCUGUGGCCCUGUACACAAUGGAAACCCAGGAAUUGUUGUCAACAGAUGGGUGUGUGCAGUUUGCACAGGAGCUGGGUAGGCUGGUCAUGGUACCUACACUCUCAGAAUAGCACUAAAACACUCAUAUUUACUGACAGAAGCCGAGAGUAAUUACCUUCACCCAGCCUGUGGCAAAAUACCCAGCUUAAUUACAGAAUUAGCCAAACAGGAUUCAGGUCCACCUGUCCACUGGGACAUACUAGAUUUCCUGUUCUUCAAGCCCAGCUGAGUGGAUUAUUGGGCACUGUUAGGACAGGCUUCUAGACCUAACAGUGCCCACUCUGUAUAGACUCACCCUUCAUUGAGAUCUUCUCCAGCACCCCAUGACUUUUAUCCACAGGAUCCCACCAUCCCUAGAACUUUCAUAAAGCACUUGGUGUUGUUUAAAAAGGAAGGUUUAGAAGGGAAGAGGGGCUCACACCUGGCUUGACCACAAGCUCUUAGGUGUCACUAAAGCAGGGCCUUUUGCAGCCUCAGGAGUUGGAUCCAGGCUCCACCCUCUCAGCAAUUAUCUUACCAUGGAUAAUAAAGCUUAGCAUGAAACCUCCCGCCCAAGCUGUGUGCUGGGGAAGGGCCUGCAUGGAGGCUCUCUCGUGGGAGAGGAGUUGCAUUUCCUGUACUAAGCCUGCUCCUGGCUCAAUCUCUCCCCAGGCUGUGCUGGCUGGAGCUGCUGCCUUCAUUUA